CAUUUUGGAUACCGUCCUCGCUGCGGAAAGUUGGGGCAACCUGUUGCUAGUCUGGUCGUUGGUGACAGCGAGGCUUCCGCGCUCGCUGCUGGUGAGCAGCCCCGGCGUGCCCCGCGGGCUGGAAGAGGCGGCGGCGUGAUGCGGCCCGUGGACGCGGACGAGGCGCGGGAGCCCCGCGAGGAGCCGGGCAGCCCGCUGAGCCCCGCGCCCCGCGCCGGCCGCGAGAACCUGGCCUCCCUGGAGCGCGAGCGCGCCCGGGCGCACUGGCGGGCCCGCAGGAAGCUGCUGGAGAUCCAGAGCCUGCUCGACGCCAUCAAGAGUGAGGUGGAGGCAGAGGAGCGGGGCGCCCGGGCCCCAGCACCCCGCCCGCGUGCGGAGGCUGAGGAGCGGGUGGCUCGGCUGUGCGCCGAAGCAGAGAGGAAGGCUGCGGAGGCGGCGCGGAUGGGCAGGCGGAUCGUGGAGCUGCACCAGCGGAUCGCCGGCUGCGAGUGCUGCUGAGCCGGCGAGGCCGCGCGGGUCUGGAGCGGAGCGCGGCGGGGAGUGUCCCGCGUGGAAGGCGCUGGGUAGGCAGGGAGGGGAGCGCAGAGCCGUGCCACGCUCUCCGCGGAGUUGGUUUCAUUCUUUUUUCAUAGGUAAUUAGAGAAAAUAAUUUGAUAUGUUGUUGUAAAGAGUCAUGACCACUGGAAGUAUUUUCAGGACGUAGACCUGGUGGGUCACUACGUGGGGGGAGAGAGGUGUGAAGCGGAGGUACAUGCUGGAAACGUGUGAAUGUUGUUACGAGAUUGGAGCGUUUGCGAUGACCUUCCUGCAGGUGGAAGCAUUGUGCACAGGUGGUUGGGUUUGUUUGACUCCCGGAUAUGAGAAUAUCAAGCUCAAAAUUUAUGUUGUGAUGAUGAAUUUCUCCCACUUGUACUUUAGGUGGCCAACUGACGAACUGUGUUCACCUGAUAAGGAGUCGUGGCUGCUUGGACAGGCUCAAACCAAGAGAGCCUUUCGUUUUGUCUCCCCUGUUUUUCUGCCUGCGUUUUCUCCACAUUAGCCACUCAAUUUCCAGUACCAUCCUGGCGGAUGACUUCAGCAUUAGAUGGUCAGGUGUAUUUUUUUAUUAAUAGGCGCAUUCAGUUUGGAAAAGACAGCUUUUCAUUAAUGUCCCACGUAAAGGAAUAUGGCCUAUACAGUACGUACGCUGCUGCGUGGUCAUAUUUGUUCCUGUGAUCUUAUUGUAUUUUCAAAGUUUGGAAGUAUACUCGUGUGCUUUGCUGUUUUUUUAUGCUUCCUGGAAUUUGGGGACUCAUGAGAGACUUGAGGUUAGAGUUCUGCAAGUGAGAAGACACUACAUGGUUGCAGCUGCCACAUGAAGAACCCAAGCUCCUGUCAAAGUUGUGAAUGCGACUUUGGAUGAGAUUAAGAAGGCCCAGUGGACGGUUGGUCUUGAAGAGUGGCAGUGUGUGGAUUUGAGGACCUCUGCAGACCAUCAGAUCAAAGGAGGGAGAGCUGUUUUGGGUGUUUUGUUUUUUUUGUUUUUAUAGCAUUUUGCUUUUUCUUGGAAUGUAAUUUUCCUAUGGCAUGUUAACUGGUGCACAUCGUGUAACCUGUCUGGUGAGCAACCUACAAUUGGGAUGAGUUCUAGGUACAUGUGUUUGCUGACUUUGGGGUAAACAACUUUGUUAUAAUACAGUCUCUGCCACAGAUGCAUGUGACCUCUUCAGGGGCCCAGAGUGGCUGAGGAAGGAAAGCUUCAAGCUGGCCAUGGGGGUCCCAAACAGUCAUUCCAGGCUUAGAUGAUGACUAGCCUAGGUCAUCAGAGCCCAGACUCCACAGAGACUAAAAUCAGAGCUCUGUCUUGUUAUGAUAAAUUUCAUUUGCUUGGAAAAAGAAAUGCUGAAAGCCAGUGUUUAGAAUCUUUGUGCAGAUGACCAAAGCAAUUGACUUGGCCAAGAAAAGGUAAGGUAAAUAAACAUUUUUCAAAAUGA